AGUCUGCUGCCGUGUGCGUGUGCGUCAGGGCUCUCCGGGCGGCAAUGGGGGCUUGAGAGCCGGGUCCCCAGCGCCGGGAAGGGAGCGCGGUGGCCGCCACCGCCACCGCCCCGGAGUCCGGCGCCGAAGCUGCGGGCGGGCGGGCGGGCACCAGCUCGGUCAGGGGCUGCUUGGCGCGGCACUGUGCGGUGCAGCGGCGGCGCGGCGCGGUGCGGGCUUUUCCCAGGCGCCCCGGGGUCGGGUGGCCAACGGCGCGGCCGCGGGCGCUGAGCGCGACCGGUUCGCGGUAGCGGUGGCGGCGGCGUGCGUGCCAGGGGCUGGGGGCUCCGCCGCCUCUCUUGCGGCUCACCGAGCUCCGCGCUUCCCUCUCUCCAGGGCAGGCGGCUUCUCAGAGCACAACAGCUCCAGCUGGCAGCAUCACUUCCCGCCAAUUUAUCCAACUUCUGCCAAGGCUCUGAAAUGCCAACAACGUCGAGGCCUGCACUUGAUGUCAAGGGUGGCACCUCACCUGCGAAGGAGGAUGCCAACCAAGAGAUGAGCUCCGUGGCCUACUCCAACCUUGCGGUGAAAGAUCGCAAAGCAGUGGCCAUUCUGCACUACCCUGGGGUAGCCUCAAAUGGAACCAAGGCCAGUGGGGCUCCCACUAGUUCCUCGGGAUCUCCAAUAGGCUCUCCUACAACCACCCCUCCCACUAAACCCCCAUCCUUCAACCUGCACCCCGCCCCUCACUUGCUGGCUAGUAUGCACCUGCAGAAACUUAAUAGCCAGUAUCAGGGGAUGGCUGCUGCCACUCCAGGCCAACCCGGGGAGGCAGGACCCCUGCAAAACUGGGACUUUGGGGCCCAGGCGGGAGGGGCAGAAUCACUCUCUCCUUCUGCUGGUGCCCAGAGCCCUGCUAUCAUCGAUUCGGACCCAGUGGAUGAGGAAGUGCUGAUGUCGCUGGUGGUGGAACUGGGGUUGGACCGAGCCAAUGAGCUUCCGGAGCUGUGGCUGGGGCAGAAUGAGUUUGACUUCACUGCGGACUUUCCAUCUAGCUGCUAAUGCCAAGUGUCCCUAAAGAUGGAGGAAUAAAGCCACCAAUUCUGUUGUAAAUAAAAAUAAAGUUACUUACAAAGAGA